GCUUCCUCGCCGGUCCACCUACCCAGACAAGGCAAACGGAAAUCUGCAGCAGGACUCAGCUUGGUGCACACAACUCCGCCCUCGCCACACCCACUCUGCAGCGUCUGGCCCGGCAAUACCCAUCUGGGCGCCCCUCCUGCUUCCUCUAGGCUCGCCUGCGCGCUGUCACGUUACGGCGGAACUAAUCCAGCGACGCCUGCGCUUUGACGCAUUUGGUGCCGUGGAAGGGAAAAAGGGGGACUGCAGUAUGCGUCACACCCGGAAGCGGCGAGCCGGAAGUGGGGAGAACCGGAGCCUUACCAUCAAACUUCGGAAACGGAAGCCAGAGAAAAAGGUAGAAUGGACAAGUGACACUGUGGACAAUGAACACAUGGGCCGCCGCUCAUCAAAAUGCUGCUGUAUUUAUGAGAAACCUCGGGCCUUUGGCGAGAGCUCCACGGAAAGUGAUGAGGAGGAAGAAGAGGGCUGUGGUCAUACACACUGUGUACGUGGCCACCGCAAAGGACGGCGUCGUGCAACCCUAGGACCGACCCCCACCACCCCUCCCCAGCCUCCUGACCCUUCCCAGCCCCCUCCAGGGCCAAUGCAGCACUAAAUCCCUCUCUCCUCCAGCAUUCCUGUGUCUGUCUGGCCCUAAAUGUAUCCAUGUGGCUACUUCUCCAGCCCCCUCCUUCCCUCUCUUCUGCCUGAUAGAGGGAAGAGGAAGAGGAGGACGAACAGAGAUCCUGAAAUUCUGACUUGCUGCUAUUCCAGAACCCAGCCUCCUGGGUUUCCCCAGUCCUCAUUUUUCCUCCCAAUACCCACCCUUCUCUCUCGAGGGAUCUAGGCACCUUGGUCCCAGUGUCUUCCUUUUGUUCUCACUGCCAAACUGCCUGUCCUGGGAUCUAGUUAUCUUGGCCCUGCACUCUCAACAUGAGUAGCGAACACUUAAAUUGGGUUUUCAACAGUCCCAGCUUUCACUGCCAGGGUCCCAGUCAGAUUCCAGGAAUUUGCGCCCUAACUUUGCUUGCUAAUCCUGGUUUAGAGCUAUCCCACUAAAAUAUUUAAUCCUAAUUCUUAGUCCUUGCCUGUGAGAUAUGAGGUCUUACAGGAGACCUCAGAGCUCCCAGCCCUUCUCCUCCUGCUAACCCUUCUCACACCCUCAAGAGGAGUUAGAAAAGAGGUCCUUGUUAUUCUCACCUCUUAUGGAAAAUGGAACAAGAAAUAAUCAUAUCCUUUCUUCCCACCCUUCUCCUGUUAUUUAGGAUUUCUGACAAAGCUGGCUUGAGAUUGGUCACUUAGAGCCGACUGUCUCCUCUGCCUUUUGUUUUUCAGCUUCAGAGACAGAUCCAAUAUAGUCCCAGGGACCUGGGUCUCUGGGAGAGGAAGGAAGAGGGAGGGAGCAAAGAGAUUGGGGUAUGUCCCCUGUAGUACACUCUUUCCUCUUACUUCCUAGACUUUGAUUUCUCCGGCAGCCCAGAUGUUCAGUUCUCUUGGCCCCUCUCUACCCCUUACUGGGAUCUGGUUUUCAUUUUCCGGUCCUUUUGCCAUACACAGUUACAGAGAUCAGUCAAAUCCAUACCACCACUGAGAUCUCAUUUAUUGCCACAGAUGCACAAAAUAAAUAACCCAAAAUCACAAAA